GAGGGUAGCCAUGACGGCCUCCGUGCUGCGAAGUAUCUCGCUAGCCCUGCGCCCGACUAGCGGGUGAGUGCGGACGCUGGCCGGAUAGCGGAGUGCCCAGGGCGCGUGCGGGGUCUUCGCGACUGUCCGCCAGGACUCGCCUGUGCUCCCUGCUCGCCUCCCAGUCCACGAAUAUCUCAGGGAUGAGCCAUCUGGUCGUGACUCUUAUGCAUGAAAAUCUGAGCACCCUGGCGAGCAGCGGUCCUGCUUAAGUCCUCUGUGGUCUGAACGAAAGAUUUUGAAAAACCUUCCACGUUGACCUUGCUGUCAUAUCAAGCUUCUGGGAACUUGGCAGACGCAGCUUAGAGAGACUCACCAGCGAGCGUCAUUGUUGUCUUUCUGGGAACUCAUUCCCAUGAGAUCAGAACCUCUUCGAAAAAAGAAGAAGGUAGAUCCUAAAAAAGACCAAGAAGCAAAGGAGCGCUUGAAAAGGAAGAUCCGAAAACUGGAAAAGGCUACUCAAGAGCUAAUUCCUAUUGAAGAUUUUAUUACCCCUCUAAAGUUCUUGGAUAAAGCAAGAGAGCGGCCUCAGGUGGAGCUCACCUUUGAGGAGACUGAGAGGAGAGCUCUGCUUCUGAAGAAGUGGUCCUUGUACAAGCAGCAAGAGCGUAAGAUGGAGAGGGACACCAUCAGGGCUAUGCUAGAAGCCCAGCAGGAAGCUCUGGAGGAACUGCAACUGGAAUCCCCGAAGCUCCAUGCUGAGGCCAUCAAGCGGGAUCCUAACCUGUUCCCCUUUGAGAAGGAAGGGCCACAUUACACACCACCGAUCCCUAACUACCAACCCCCUGAAGGCAGGUACAAUGACAUCACCAAGGUGUACACACAAGUGGAGUUUAAGAGAUAGACUUGCAGGCUGCUAUCCUUAACAUGCUGCCCCUGAGAGUAGGAAUGACCAGGGUUCAAGUCUGCUUUCCACAGAAUCAGGCAUGCUGUUAAUAAAUACUGGUUUAAUCAAAA